ACUCGCGAAGUGGAAUUUGCCCAGACAAGCAACAUGGCUCGGAAACGCGCGGCCGGCGGGGAGCCGCGGGGACGCGAACUGCGCAGCCAGAAAUCCAAGGCCAAGAGCAAGGCCCGGCGUGAGGAGGAGGAGGAGGAUGCCUUUGAAGAUGAGAAACCCCCAAAGAAGAGCCUUCUCUCCAAAGUUUCACAAGGAAAGAGGAAAAGAGGCUGCAGUCAUCCUGGGGGUUCAGCAGAUGGUCCAGCAAAAAAGAAAGUGGCCAAGGUGACUGUUAAAUCUGAAAACCUCAAGGUUAUAAAGGAUGAAGCCCUCAGCGAUGGGGAUGACCUCAGGGACUUUCCAAGUGACCUCAAGAAGGCACACCAUCUGAAGAGAGGGGCUACCAUGAAUGAAGACAGCAAUGAAGAAGAGGAAGAAAGUGAAAAUGAUUGGGAAGAGGUUGAAGAACUUAGUGAGCCUGUGCUGGGUGACGUGAGAGAAAGUACAGCCUUCUCUCGAUCUCUUCUGCCUGUGAAGCCAGUGGAGAUAGAGAUUGAAACGCCAGAGCAGGCGAAGACAAGAGAAAGAAGUGAAAAGAUAAAACUGGAGUUUGAGACAUAUCUUCGGAGGGCGAUGAAACGUUUCAAUAAAGGGGUCCAUGAGGACACACACAAGGUUCACCUUCUCUGCCUGCUAGCAAAUGGCUUCUAUCGAAAUAACAUCUGCAGCCAGCCAGAUCUGCAUGCUAUUGGCCUGUCCAUCAUCCCAGCCCGCUUUACCAGAGUGCUGCCUCGAGAUGUGGACACCUACUACCUCUCAAACCUGGUGAAGUGGUUCAUUGGAACAUUUACAGUUAAUGCAGAACUUUCAGCCAGUGAACAAGAUAACCUGCAGACUACAUUGGAAAGGAGAUUUGCUAUUUACUCUGCUCGAGAUGAUGAGGAAUUGGUCCAUAUAUUCUUACUGAUUCUCCGGGCUCUGCAGCUCUUGACCCGGCUGGUAUUGUCUCUACAGCCAAUUCCUCUGAAGUCAGCAACAGCAAAGGGAAAGAAACCUUCCAAGGAAAGAUUGACUGCGGAUCCAGGAGGCUCCUCAGAAACUUCCAGCCAAGUUCUAGAAAACCACACCAAACCAAAGACCAGCAAAGGAACCAAACAAGAGGAAACCUUUGCUAAGGGCACCUGCAGGCCAAGUGCCAAAGGGAAGAGGAACAAGGGAGGCAGAAAGAAACGGAGCAAGCCCUCCUCCAGCGAGGAAGAUGAGGGCCCAGGAGACAAGCAGGAGAAGGCAACCCAGCGACGUCCGCAUGGCCGGGAGCGGCGGGUGGCCUCCAGGGUGUCUUAUAAAGAGGAGAGUGGGAGUGAUGAGGCUGGCAGCGGCUCUGAUUUUGAGCUCUCCAGUGGAGAAGCCUCUGAUCCCUCUGAUGAGGAUUCCGAACCUGGCCCUCCAAAGCAGAGGAAAGCCCCCGCUCCUCAGAGGACAAAGGCUGGGUCCAAGAGUGCCUCCAGGACCCAUCGUGGGAGCCAUCGUAAGGACCCAAGCUUGCCAGCGGCAUCCUCAAGCUCUUCAAGCAGUAAAAGAGGCAAGAAAAUGUGCAGCGAUGGUGAGAAGGCAGAAAAAAGAAGCAUAGCUGGUAUAGACCAGUGGCUAGAGGUGUUCUGUGAGCAGGAGGAAAAGUGGGUAUGUGUAGACUGUGUGCACGGUGUGGUGGGCCAGCCUCUGACCUGUUACAAGUACGCCACCAAGCCCAUGACCUAUGUGGUGGGCAUUGACAGUGACGGCUGGGUCCGAGAUGUCACACAGAGGUACGACCCAGUCUGGAUGACAGUGACCCGCAAGUGCCGGGUUGAUGCUGAGUGGUGGGCCGAGACCUUGAGACCAUACCAGAGCCCAUUUAUGGACAGGGAGAAGAAAGAAGACUUGGAGUUUCAGGCUAAACACAUGGACCAGCCUUUGCCCACUGCCAUUGGCUUAUAUAAGAACCACCCUCUGUAUGCCCUGAAGCGGCAUCUCCUGAAAUAUGAGGCCAUCUAUCCCGAGACAGCUGCCAUCCUUGGGUAUUGUCGUGGAGAAGCGGUCUACUCCAGGGAUUGUGUGCACACUCUGCAUUCCAGGGACACGUGGCUGAAGAAAGCAAGAGUGGUGAGGCUUGGAGAAGUACCCUACAAGAUGGUGAAAGGCUUUUCUAACCGUGCUCGGAAAGCCCGACUUGCUGAGCCCCAGCUGCGGGAAGAAAAUGACCUGGGCCUGUUUGGCUACUGGCAGACAGAGGAGUAUCAGCCCCCAGUGGCCGUGGACGGGAAGGUGCCCCGGAACGAGUUUGGGAAUGUGUACCUCUUCCUGCCCAGCAUGAUGCCUAUUGGCUGUGUCCAGCUGAACCUGCCCAAUCUACACCGCGUGGCCCGCAAGCUGGACAUCGACUGUGUCCAGGCCAUCACUGGCUUUGAUUUCCAUGGCGGCUACUCCCAUCCCGUGACUGAUGGAUACAUCGUCUGCGAGGAAUUCAAAGACGUGCUCCUGACUGCCUGGGAAAAUGAGCAGGCAGUCAUUGAAAGGAAGGAGAAGGAGAAAAAGGAGAAGCGGGCUCUAGGGAACUGGAAGUUGCUGGCCAAAGGUCUGCUCAUCAGGGAGAGGCUGAAGCGUCGCUACGGGCCCAAGAGUGAGGCAGCAGCUCCCCACACAGAUGCAGGAGGUGGACUCUCUUCUGAUGAAGAGGAGGGGACCAGCUCUCAAGCAGAAGCGGCCAGGAUACUGGCUGCCUCCUGGCCUCAAAACCGAGAAGAUGAAGAAAAGCAGAAGCUGAAGGGUGGGCCCAAGAAGACCAAAAGGGAAAAGAAAGCAGCAGCUUCCCACCUGUUCCCAUUUGAGCAGCUGUGAGCUGAGCGCCCACUAGAGGGGCACCCACCAGUUGCUGCUGCCCCACUACAGGCCCCACACCUGCCCUGGGCAUGCCCAGCCCCUGGUGGUGGGGGCUUCUCUGCUGAGAAGGCAAACUGAGGCAGCAUGCACGGAGGCGGGGUCAGGGGAGACGAGGCCAAGCUGAGGAGGUGCUGCAGGUCCCGUCUGGCUCCAGCCCUUGUCAGAUUCACCCAGGGUGAAGCCUUCAAAGCUUUUUGCUACCAAAGCCCACUCACCCUUUGAGCUACAGAACACUUUGCUAGGAGAUACUCUUCUGCCUCCUAGACCUGUUCUUUCCAUCUUUAGAAACAUCAGUUUUUGUAUGGAAGCCACCGGGAGAUUUCUGGAUGGUGGUGCAUCCGUGAAUGCGCUGAUCGUUUCUUCCAGUUAGAGUCUUCAUCUGUCCGACAAGUUCACUCGCCUCGGUUGCGGACCUAGGACCAUUUCUCUGCAGGCCACUUACCUUCCCCUGAGUCAGGCUUACUAAUGCUGCCCUCACUGCCUCUUUGCAGUAGGGGAGAGAGCAGAGAAGUACAGGUCAUCUGCUGGGAUCUAGUUUUCCAAGUAACAUUUUGUGGUGACAGAAGCCUAAAAAAAGCUAAAAUCAGGAAAGAAAAGGAAAAAUACGAAUUGAAAAUUAAGGAAAUGUUAGUAAAAUAGAUGAGUGUUAAACUAGAUUGUAUUCAUUACUAGAUAAAAUGUAUAAAGCUCUCUGUACUAAGGAGAAAUGACUUUUAUAACAUUUUGAGAAAAUAAUAAAGCAUUUAUCUAAA